GCGCGUCCCGCCCCGCGGGCUCCCGGUGGCUGCUUCCCGUCCGCUGUCCUCUGCUGCCAGUCCCCUGCCCCGGGCAAAGCCCAUCUGGUCCGCCGAGCAGGCCGGAGCUAUUGGGAGUGGCGGAUCCUCCCACCCCAGCCGGAUCUGGGCCAUGGCCGAGCCUGGAGAGGGACUGCCAGAGGAGGUGCUGGCACUCAUCUUCCGCCACCUGUCCCUGAGAGACCGUGCUGCCGCCGCCAGGGUCUGCAGGGCCUGGGCCGCCGCUGCUACCUGCAGCGCCGUGUGGCACGACACAAAAAUCAGUUGCGAAUGUGAGCUGGAAGGCAUGCUGCCACCUUAUCUGUCCGCCUGCCUCGACCACAUUCACAACCUACGGCUGGAAUUUGAGCCAUCGAGGAAGCCGAGCCGCCGGGCGGCCAUCGAGCUGCUGAUGGUUCUGGCGGGCCGUGCCCCGGGGCUGCGAGGCCUGCGCCUGGAGUGCCGCGGAGAAAAACCGCUCUUCGACGCGGGCCGCGACGUCCUGGAGGCUGUGCACGCUGUAUGCGGGGCGGCCAGCCAGCUACGCCACCUCGACCUGCGGCGCUUGUCCUUCACACUGGACGACGCGCUGGUGCUGCAGGCGGCGCGCAGCUGUCCCGAGCUCCACAGCCUUUUUCUGGACAACAGUACCCUAGUGGGCAGCGUGGGUCCCGGCUCAGUGCUCGAGCUACUGGAGGCCUGCCCGCGCCUGCGCGCUCUCGGCCUGCACCUAGCCAGUUUGUCGCACGCCAUCCUCGAAGCACUGGCGGCGCCAGACCGAGCGCCUUUCGCGCUCUUGGCUCUGCGGUGCGCGUGCCCCGAAGAUGCACGCGCGUCCCCGCUGCCCAACGAAGCCUGGGUCGCGUUGCGCCGCCGCCACCCUGGGCUGGCAGUGGAGCUGGAGCUGGAGCCCGCGCUGCCCGCUGAGAGCGUGACGCGCGUCCUGCAGCCAGCCGUCCCCGUGGCUGCGCUGCGCCUCAACCUCUCAGGCGACACCGUAGGCCCAGUGCGCUUCGCAGCACACCACUACGCCGCAACCCUGUGCGCGCUCGAGGUGCGCGCAGCCGCUUCGGCCGAGCUGAACGCCGCGCUGGAGGAGCUGGCGGCGCGCUGCGCGGCCCUGCGCGAGGUGCAUUGUUUCUGCGUGGUGAGCCACUCGGUGCUGGACGCCUUCCGCGCGCACUGCCCGCGCCUGCGCACCUAUACCCUCAAGCUCACGCGCGAGCCGCAUCCCUGGAGGCCUACGCUCGUGGCGUGAUUGGGCGACUUCUCUCCCCCGUCCCCGUGGACGUAAGCGCUCUGAGAGGGAACGGGGGGGGUGUCCAGGCGCGCCCCGAGUGCUAGUGCCUUCUUUUGGGAUUGUUGCCCCCCGGGUCUUUACCGAGUUGGGAACUGUGAUGGCAUCGGGACCAGUCCUGGGCGCCCUGAGACCACUCGCUGCUCUCACCCUCUGCAGACGCCCCACCCGCUCGGUCCUGGACACACUGCCCCCCUCUCUUGCCUCCACCCCUCUGCGGACUCUGCAGCUCCGCGGCCCCGGCGCAGGGAGAGGGAGGGCACGGGCGCGGGCCGGGCCUCAAGGGUGAGUGUGAAAUAAACAAAUCCUGCAGUG